UUUUUUUUUUUUUUUUUUCGAGACAAAGUCUCAUUCUAUUGCCCAGGUUAGAGUGCAGUGGCACAAUCUUGGCUCACUACAACCUCCGCCUCCUGGGCAGCCUCCCAAGUAGCUGGGACCACAGUCACCCACGAUGCCAGCUAUUUUUUUUUUUCUUGAGACUGAGUCUUGCUCUCUUGCCCACGUUGGAGUGCAGUGGUGCAAUUUCUGUUCACUGCAUCGUUUCCGCCUCCUGGGUUCAGGCGAUUCUCCUGCCUCAGCCUUCCAAGUAGCUGGGACUACAGGUGCCCACCACCACGCCUGGCUAAUUUUUGUAUUUUUAGUAGAAAUGGGGUUUUGCCAUAUUGGCCAGGCUGGUCUCAAGCUCCUGACCUCAAGUGAUCUGCCCGCCUCGAUCUCCCAAAGCGCUAGGAUUACAGGUGUGAGUCACCAUGCCAGGCCGGUAAUCGCCAUUUGACUGACGUGAGAUGGUAUCUCAUUGCGGUUUUGAUUUACAUUUCUCUAAUGAUCAGUAAUGUUGAGCUUAAAAAGCUCUUAGUUUAUUGCCUAACAUAUAAUGUUUCUUUCUUUGCAAGUUUUCUUUUCUUUUUUCUUUUUUUGGAGAUGGAGUUUCACUCUUGUUGCCCAGGCUGGAGUGCAUUGGCACUAUCUCAGCUCACUGCAACCUUUGCUUCCUGGGUUCAAGCAAUUCUCCUGCCUCAGCCUCCCGAGUAGCUGGAAUUACAGGCAUGUGCCACCAUGCCUGGCUAAUUUCUUUUUUAUAUUUAGUAGAGACGGGGUUUCUCCAUGUUGGCCAGGCUGGUCUUGAACUCCUGACCUCAGGUGUUUCACCCACCUCGGCCUCCCAAAGUGUUGGGAUUACAGGCGUGAGCCACCGCGCCCGGCUGCAAGUUUUCUUAAAAGGGCCCUGCCUUCCCUGACAUUCUCUCUAUGUCAGCAAGAUCUCAGCCCACCAUUUCUCAGUUCCUUCUAUUCCCAUUGAUGGUGCUUUUGAAGCGGUGUUUCACUACUCCCUUGUUUCUGCCUGACUUUGGGUUAUCUCCUGUUAAGCUUAUAUAUGCUAACUGGGGGCUUACUUUAUUUUUACAGAAAAUGCAUUCGUACAUAUAAAAUUUAUUCUGUAUUGAACAAGUUUUUAACACAUUGUUAAUCUUAACCUUAAUUUUAGAAAUAAUAGCUUUAAAAAAGUGAACAAAUAAAGGUUACAUUCUGAUAACAUCAGUAAAACAGUAUGUACUGUUGUUUAUGAGAUGAAACUAUAAAAUUUUUAUUUUGGAAAAAAGAGUUUUUUGUUUUUGUUUUUGUUUUUUUUUUUUUGAGACGGAGUCUCACUCUGUCGCCCAGGCUGGAGUCCAGUGGCUUGAUCUCGGCUCAUUGCAAGCUCCGCCUCCCGGGUUCACGCCAUUCUCCCUCCUCAGCCUCCCGAGUAGCUGGGACUACAGGCGCCCGCCACCACGCCCAGCUAAUUUUUUGUAUUUUUAGUAGAGACGGAGUUUCACCAUUCACAGAAUGGUGUCGAUCUCCUGACCUUGUGAUCCGCCUGCCUCGGCCUCCCAAAGUGCUGGGAUUACAGGCCUGAGCCACCGUGCCUGGCCAAGAGCUUUAUUUGAUAUGUUGAUUCUUCAUGUAUACAAUAAUGGAAAAUAUGUUAUCUUUUGUUUUUUUUUUUUAAUUGAGAUAAUGGGCUGUCUCUGUGUUCCCCAGGCUGGUCUCGAACUCCUGGGGGACUCAAGCAAUCCUCCUGCCUCAACCUCCUAAGUAGCUGGAAUUACAAGUAUGCACCCUGUUAGUUAUCUUUUUUGUAGGAAAGGUGGUUAUAAUUAUUGUCUAAAAUGUUACUUGCUGAUUAUAGUGGCUUUUACUGUUGAUAUGUGUGUUUUUUUUUUGAUCAUAUUAGUUUCUAUUAGAAGUAGGAAUGUAUCUUACUUUUCUGAAACAGGGUCUUGCUGUCACCCAGGCUGGAAUGUUAGUGGCAUGAUAAUGGCCCACUGCAACCUCAACCUCCUGGGCUCAAGUGAUCCUCCAGUAUCAGUGGGCACCCCCAUCUCCAGCACCCCCACCUCCUGCAGUAUCUGGGACCACAGGCAUGCGCCACCACACCUUGCUAAUUAAAAUUGUUUUUUUUUUUUGUAGAGACGAGGUCUUGCUACAUUGUCCAGGAUGGAGAAGUAGGAAUUCUUAAGGAUAUUGUUAUGGAGGGAAAAAAAUCAUUGAUUAUGGAAGAUUCCCACAAGAGUACCACGUCAGAGACAGCACCUCAACCUGGUUCAGCAGUUCAGGGAGCUCACAUUUCUCAUAUUGCUCAACAGGUAUCAUCUUUAUCAGAAAGUGAGGAGUCCCAGGACUCAUCCGACAGCAUAGGCUCCUCACAGAAAGCCCACGGGAUCCUAGCACGGCGCCCAUCUUACAGAAAAAUUUUGAAAGACUUAUCUUCUGAAGAUACACGGGGCAGAAAAGGAGACGGAGAAAAUUCUGGAGUUUCUGCUGCUGUCACUUCUAUGUCUGUUCCAACUCCCAUCUAUCAGACUAGCAGCGGACAGUACAUUGCCAUUGCCCCAAAUGGAGCCUUACAGUUGGCAAGUCCAGGCACAGAUGGAGUACAGGGACUUCAGACAUUAACCAUGACAAAUUCAGGCAGUACUCAGCAAGGUACAACUAUUCUUCAGUAUGCACAGACCUCUGAUGGACAGCAGAUACUUGUGCCCAGCAAUCAGGUGGUCGUACAAACUGCAUCAGGAGAUAUGCAAACAUAUCAGAUCCGAACUACACCUUCAGCUACUUCUCUGCCACAAACUGUGGUGAUGACAUCUCCUGUGACUCUCACCUCUCAGACAACUAAGACAGAUGACCCCCAAUUGAAAAGAGAAAUAAGGUUAAUGAAAAACAGAGAAGCUGCUCGAGAAUGUCGCAGAAAGAAGAAAGAAUAUGUGAAAUGCCUGGAAAACCGAGUUGCAGUCCUGGAAAAUCAAAAUAAAACUCUAAUAGAAGAGUUAAAAACUUUGAAGGAUCUUUAUUCCAAUAAAAGUGUUUGAUUCCUAAGAAAGAAAAUAUUUUUGUGGACAUGCAUAAAAAUUAAAUGGAUUUCCUAGUGGAGUUUUAUAAAUUAAAAGGUCAAAACUGAAGCUUUUUAUUUAGGCUUUUCCAAAUCAAGGAUAAAUAUCUUACGCACGAUAUCUAGUGACAGAGGAGAAAGUGGAAAAUGACCUCAAGGAAGCUACGGGCACAACUGGAAGCUUUGUAGAAAUUAAACAUAUUCAAGGAGCAAGAAAUGAACUUUCAGCAGUCUAAAUUUUCUAAAUAACCAAUAGUUGCCAAUCUAAAAUGGCAGAGAAGAUGAAAUUUGAUAAACUGAAUUUUUUUUAAAAAUCCAUUUACCCUACAGGUUUGCAUUUGUUUGCUGAAAUUUACCUUUUUUUAGUUAUAUAUAUGUGUGUGUGUGUGUGUAAUUUCUGCCAAUAAAUUCUAAAUUACAAAGGUAAGAGAAAACCUAGUACAUUACUAAAUAUAUAAAGUAUAUGUUCUGAUUAUGUAUACUUGUUCUAGUGUCAAGUCUUUUUAAGUGGGUUUUUAAAAGUUUGUUAUUGGACUUGAAUGGAUUUUUGAGACUAGGUUAAUUAUUUUUGAGGUCUUAUCCUAAAAGGCAUCUAAGGUACAUGAAUGGAGUAUGGUGAUUUUAUAACAUUUUUUAUCAGAAUGGAAAAAGAACUGUUUAAAAGUUUGAUACUUUUAAAUAGUUGGUUUUUUUGCUUACUCUGGUAAUGAUUUUCUACAAAUACAUAAUAAAUUGUUUUUUUGAGUCUAUAUUCUGUAUGCAGUUGAAUAUCCAUUACUUAUUCUGCUGUGCUUUAAUAGAAUGGAAUGUUUACAGGCCCUUAAAAUAUUAUUUUUAAAAAACCUUCUGAAGAUACAUACCAAAGUUUUUCCAAGAAGAUUUUAUAAUCAAUUUAAUAAUGUAAGGUUUAUCAGAUUCUAUAAUAGUAUAGUUAUUAAGGCAAUUUUAUGUUAGAGACUAUUUUGUAAUGUAGUGAGUGGUACCUUUAUAAGAAAAGUGACUGCCAAUAUAUUUUUAUAGCUGAUCUUUAUAAAUUCUAAUGUUGAGUUUUUAAUGAUUAUUUUAAAUGUUUAUAUAGUUUAGUAAAAUUUGCAUCUCAAAGUAUCAUUUUUAUAUUAUGGGACGUUUUCAGAUUGGCUAAUAUUUGCAUUGUAAAUUUUGUAUGCAGUUUAUCUAAAAUUCAAAAAUACUGUCAGUACACCAGCGUUUAACAUCUAUAUUCCAAUUUGUAUACAGUUUAAAAUUGUACUGCAAAACUAUUGUGUGCUCUUACACAGUAUGCAUCAUAUUGUUGUCUGUGAAAUUAAAGGACAUUUGAUAGUCUACUGAAUGUAAAAUAUAAUGCUUGGUAUAUGAAUGAUAA